CCAGUUCUCGGAGCCAGGUUAGGGGUUUGGCGGAGGAGGACUGCGGGGCGCGGGCCUAGGGCCCCAGCAGCCACAGCCAGGGGAGCGCUCAAGACAGAAAGCCGGUGGCUUCCUCACCUCCACCUGUAAUGCAGGAGGGAGAAUUGGCUAUUUCUCCUAUAAGCCCUGUGGCAGCCAUGCCUCCCCUAGGCACCCACGUGCAAGCCAGAUGUGAAGCUCAAAUUAACCUGCUGGGUGAAGGGGGGAUCUGCAAGCUGCCAGGAAGACUCCGCAUCCAGCCCGCACUGUGGAGCAGGGAGGACGUGCUGCACUGGCUGCGCUGGGCAGAGCAGGAGUACUCUCUGCCAUGCACCGCGGAGCACGGGUUCGAGAUGAACGGACGCGCCCUCUGCAUCCUCACCAAGGACGACUUCCGGCACCGUGCGCCCAGCUCAGGUCAGGGAAACGCACAGGCUUUCCUCUAAGCGGGAACCCUGGUGACGUCCUGUAUGAGCUGCUCCAGUACAUCAAGACCCAGCGGCGAGCCCUGGUGUGUGGGCCCUUUUUUGGAGGGAUCUUCAGGCUGAAGACGCCCACCCAGCACUCUCCAGUCCCCCCGGAAGAGGUGACUGGCCCCUCUCAGAUGGACACCCGAAGGGGCCACCUGCUGCAGCCACCAGACCCAGGGCUUACCAGCAACUUCGGCCACCUGGAUGACCCUGGCCUGGCAAGGUGGACCCCUGGCAAGGAGGAGUCCCUCAACUUAUGUCACUGUGCAGAGCUCGGCUGCAGGACCCAGGGGGUCUGUUCCUUCCCCGCGAUGCCGCAGGCCCCCAUUGACGGCAGGAUCGCUGACUGCCGCCUGCUGUGGGAUUACGUGUAUCAGCUGCUCCUUGAUACCCGAUAUGAGCCCUACAUCAAGUGGGAAGACAAGGACGCCAAGAUCUUCCGAGUUGUGGAUCCAAAUGGGCUCGCCAGACUCUGGGGAAAUCACAAGAACCGGGUGAACAUGACCUACGAGAAGAUGUCUCGUGCCCUGCGCCACUAUUAUAAGCUUAAUAUCAUUAAGAAGGAACCGGGGCAGAAACUCCUGUUCAGAUUUCUAAAGACUCCGGGAAAGAUGGUCCAGGACAAGCACAGCCACCUGGAGCCGCUGGAGAGCCAGGAGCAGGACAGAAUAGAGUUCAAGGACAAGAGGCCAGAAAUCUCUCCGUGAGGGGCAGGUGGACUCCAGGCACCCGGUACCGAUGGGGCAGGGACCGAGUCUCCCAUGAAGGCAGACUCCUCCUCCCAGCAGAGCAGCAGGAUCCCCAGCCAGACUCUGUACCCACAGGAUUACAGCCAUUGCUUGGGAAGGCUGGGAGGCCUCCCAUCCAGGACACUGGGGGCAGGAGUGUCAUCUUUUGGGCAGGGCAAUCCUGGGGCUAAAUGAGGUACAGGGGAAUGGACUCUCCCCUACUGCACCCCUGGGAGAGGAAGCCAGGCACCGAUAGAGCACCCAGCCCCACCCCUGUAAAUGGAAUUUACCAGAUGAAGGGAAUGAAGUCCCUCACUGAGCCUCAGAUUUCCUCACCUGUGAAAUGGGCUGAGGCAGGAAAUGGGAAAAAGUGUUAGUGCUUCCAGGCGGCACUGACAGCCUCAGUAACAAUAAAAACAAUGGUAGCUGA